AGAAUUCCAAAGCCAGCCUGGUCUCCAGCUCAGUGCGGUCCACACGCAGACCCUCCUUGGAUUUCGAAAGCCCGUGUGGCUUUGCCAGAGGACAUUCCAAUCCUCGAUUGUGGCUGGGGAUGGAGGGAGAUCAACCCAUCGCACUUACAGAUAAAGAAACUGAGGACGGAGUUUGUCCCAACUCCGGGGCCAGGGCAGAGUGGCUCCUCACAGCCUGAAGCUCAUCCUUCUGCACGGGCCAGCCAGGCCAGCACAGAGGCACCAGGGCAGCAGUGCACACAGGUCCCCGGGGACCCCACCAUGUGGAGCGGAUGGUGGCUGUGGCCCCUUGUGGCCGUCUGCACUGCAGACUUCUUUCGGGACGAGGCAGAGAGGAUCAUGAGGGACUCCCCUGUCAUUGAUGGGCACAAUGACCUCCCCUGGCAGCUGCUGGAUAUGUUCAACAACCGGCUGCAGGACGAGAGGGCCAACCUGACCACCUUGGCCGGCACACACACCAACAUCCCCAAGCUGAGGGCCGGCUUUGUGGGAGGCCAGUUCUGGUCCGUGUACACGCCCUGCGACACCCAGAACAAAGACGCCGUGCGGAGGACGCUGGAGCAGAUGGACGUGGUCCACCGCAUGUGCCGGAUGUACCCGGAGACCUUCCUGUAUGUCACCAGCAGUGCAGGCAUUCGGCAGGCCUUCCGGGAAGGGAAGGUGGCCAGCCUGAUCGGCGUGGAGGGCGGCCACUCCAUUGACAGCAGUUUGGGCGUCCUGCGGGCACUCUAUCAGCUGGGCAUGCGGUACCUGACCCUCACCCACAGCUGCAACACGCCCUGGGCUGACAACUGGCUGGUGGACACGGGAGACAGCGAGCCCCAGAGCCAAGGCUUGUCACCCUUUGGGCAGCGUGUGGUGAAGGAGCUGAACCGUCUGGGGGUCCUCAUCGACUUGGCUCACGUGUCUGUGGCCACCAUGAAGGCCACCCUGCAGCUGUCCAGAGCCCCGGUCAUCUUCAGCCACUCCUCGGCCUACAGCGUGUGCGCAAGCCGGCGCAACGUGCCUGACGACGUCCUGAGGCUGGUGAAACAGACAGACAGCCUGGUGAUGGUGAACUUCUACAACAAUUACAUUUCCUGCACCAACAAGGCCAACCUGUCCCAAGUGGCCGACCAUCUGGAUCACAUCAAGGAGGUGGCAGGAGCCAGAGCCGUGGGUUUUGGUGGGGACUUUGAUGGUGUUCCAAGGGUCCCUGAGGGGCUGGAGGACGUCUCCAAGUAUCCAGACCUGAUCGCUGAGCUGCUCAGGAGGAACUGGACGGAGGCGGAGGUCAAGGGCGCACUGGCUGACAACCUGCUGAGGGUCUUCGAGGCUGUGGAACAGCCUGGCUGCUGAUCAUCCAGGAUCCACUUAUCAAUAAUCAUCCUGUCUGUUCCCCUCCCAGCCUGGCGUUUUCCGUCUGGGAUUGGAGACUCGGGGGGUCCCUGGUGGGCUGCAAGGGUAUUAGGCCUAAUUUUAUUAACAGUAUUUGUAGGGUCCUACAGGGUCUGUAGGUUUUUCUCCUCGUGUACGGAGACGAGCGAUCAUAGAAAUAAAGACACAAGACAAAGAGAAGAAAAGACAGCUGGGCCCAGGGGACCACUACCACCUGGACGCGGAGACCGGUAGUGGCCCCGAAUGCCUGGCUGCACUGUUAUUUAUUGGAUACGAGGCAAAAGGGGCAGGGUCAGGAGUGUGAGCCAUCUCCAGUGAUUGAUAAGGUCACGCGAGUCACGUGUCCACUGGACAGGGGGCCCUUCCCUGUUUGGCAGCCGAGGCGGAGAGAGAGAGAGGACAGCUUACGCCAUUAUUUCUUCUAUGCAUUUCAAAGACUUUAGUACUUUCACUAAUUCUGCUACUGCUGUCUAGAAGGCAGAGCCAGGCGUACUGGGUGGAACAUGAAGGCGGACUGGGAGCGUGACCGCUGAAACACAGCAUCACAGGGAGACGGUUAGGCCUCCGGAGGGCUGCGGGGGGGGGUUGACUGAUGUCAGAUCUUCCACAAGAGAUGGUGGAGCAGAGUCUUUUCUAACGCGCCCCCGGGGAAAGGGAGAUUCCCUUUCCGGCUCUGCUAAGUAACGGGUGCCUUCCCCAGGCACUGACGUGACCGCUAGACCAAGGAGCCCUCUAGUGGCCCUGUCCGGGCGUAACGGGGGCUCACGCUCAUCUUGUGGUCGCUUCUCACGGUGCCCCUUCAGCUCCUGUCUCUGUAUGGCCUGGUUUGUCCUAGGUUAUAAUUGUAGAGCAAGGAUUAUUAUAAUAUUGGAAUAAAGAGUAAUGCCACAAACUGA